GCAGGUCGCGCGCAGCUGGCGCCUGAGGAACUGCGGCUGCGGUUCCGAGCGGGGUCUGGGGCUGUUACCAUUGAGUGACCAGAAAGGGUGAGGCCCCCGCGGUGGCCCGGGGGUUGGGGCCGAGGGUCGCGGGCCCUCAGAGCACUGCGGCCGCGGAGGCACAGCCUCCGCCUCCAAAUCCGGGCCUCUGGGGGCGGCAGGCCCUGCGUUCCUGGGAAGCCGGGGUUCCUAGUGGUCUUGGCUAGGGGCGGGGGUGGGGAAUCAGCCCCGUCGCUGGGCCUCGGACAGGGCGACCUCGCCCACAGUGAGCGCCGCCGGCGGCCCGCAUCCCCCUCUCCGACGUCGAGGUCAUCUCCCAAACCUUUGAAUCUGGGAAGCCUUCUCCGGCUGCCGUCUCCCCGGGUACCCCCUUCCCCCAGCUCACUGUAAACAUCUUUUAUUUAAUGACCUCUGAGACACCCCCUACCCUUAUCCUGGGUCCCUCGGGGCAGAGGCCAGUGAAUCGUAAACGUCCGGAGCCCUGGAAUGCGGCCCAAGCGAAAAGGCCACCGCGGUGUUGGGGGGGGGCGGUCCGCGAGUCCAGGACCGAGGGGUGGCGACUGGCGCUGGGGAACUCGGAGCCCAUCCUGCUGGCACUGCGGCCUCUCUCGCCGCAGCGUCUGGCUCCGCCCAAGCCCGAGCCCCGGGUGGGAUUGGAAGCCGGGCCCCAGCCUUUCCCAGAAUUCAGGCUUGCAGAGCGUCUGCAGGUGUCUGCCUGCCACCUGCAGCGGGACAGUUCCAAACACCUGUUGAAAGUGCAGAUUCCCCUAUCUAGUGCGGGGUGCGGGAGGCGGGAACCCGGAGCCCGGGUACGCAGAAUAUGGGUUUUUACGGAGUGUUUUAGAGGAUGUUGUGCAUACUAGAUUUUGGAGUCAGGAAAUAAAGAAGAGUGCAAGUGUCUGGUUUGUGCCCCUAGCUCUCGGUGCAAAGCGUUCCUGCAGAAUUGCUUCCACGUAAAGGGACCUUCGGGAAAUUUCGCUGGAUACCGGCUGGCAUUGACAAACCCAGCGUCCCUGAGCCUUGUGAGGUUUCCAGGCAGGCUGAUUGCGAGGCAACAUGUCUGCUUCGGUGAAAGAAAGCCUUCAGCUUCAGCUACUGGAGAUGGAAAUGCUGUUUUCUAUGUUUCCUAACCAAGGAGAAGUAAAACUUGAAGAUGUAAAUGCCCUGACGAAUAUAAAGAGGUAUUUGGAAGGCACAAGGGAGGCGCUGCCACCAAAAAUCGAAUUUGUAAUUACACUCCAGAUUGAAGAGCCCAAGGUAGGUACCCUGAUUUAAGUGUUUGCCAGGUGCCCAGUUUUUAAUUGAAACAUCUAGAACAUGAGCUUUCUGUCAAGGAAAGAUAGAAAUAUUCCAGGUGCAUAUUUCCUUGUUUGAAAGAUACGGAAUGCUCUAUAAAUUGUCUUCAGUAAAUAUCUUUAAUUUUAUGUAAACAUAUACACCUUUUUAACAAAUAUACCUGGAGUUUUUAUUGACGCUAUCUUGCAGUCUUAUGCCAUUAUUAUUUUGUUCACCCAUCCAGUUGGACUACCUUUCACAUGUAUCAUGAUUUUCAUAAAUCUAAAUAUCUCCUGUAACAUAACUGUCUUUUAAGGAGUGAAUGAGUGGAUUUUUUGAUGGCACCAUAACACAGAAAGCAAAUAUGGAUGGAAAAAUCUAAAGACUAAAAAUGAAUUUACCUCCAUCUUCUGAUCCAUUUAUCUCCAGCAACAUUAGCAUAGCAUAGGUAAUACGUGGACUGGGCAUUUGAGAACCACUGUUGUAGCUAUUUCCUACUCAUCCUUCAGUUGUUAUUCCCUCAGAGGAGACUUUCUGGUUCUCCAGACUGGAUUCUGUCCCGCUGGUUACACACUUCAAUGGAACCCUCCACUUUUCCAUGGUGAAAAUUGAUUUGCAAGUGACCAUGCCUCACAGCUACCCCUAUGUAGCAUUGCAGCUGUUUGGACGGUCAUCUGAACUUGACAGACAUCAGCAGCUACUUCUCAACAAAGGUCUCACUUCUUACAUAGGGACUUUUGAUCCAGGUGAGCUCUGUGUAUGUGCAGCAAUCCAGUGGCUACAGGACAACAGUGCAUCUUAUUUCCUGAACAGAAAGCUUGUAUAUGAACCAUCUACACAAGCAAAGCCAGUCAAGAACACAUUCCUCCGAAUGUGGAUCUACAGUCACCAUAUAUAUCAGCAGGACCUAAGGAAAAAGAUUUUGGAUGUUGGGAAAAGGUUAGAUGUGACUGGAUUUUGCAUGACAGGAAAGCCUGGUAUAAUCUGUGUGGAGGGUUUCAAAGAGCACUGUGAGGAGUUCUGGCACACAAUUAGGUACCCCAAUUGGAAGCACAUUUCCUGUAAGCAUGCUGAAAGCGUGGAGACAGAAGGAAAUGGUGAGGACCUGCGCCUUUUCCAUUCUUUUGAAGAGUUACUCCUUGAGGCUCAUGGUGACUAUGGAUUAAGGAAUGACUAUCACAUGAAUCUGGGCCAAUUCUUAGAAUUUCUCAAGAAGCACAAAAGUGAGCAUGUUUUUCAGAUACUAUUUGGUAUUGAAAGCAAAAGUUCAGACUCAUAAAAAGCGAUUAAGAGGCCUAUGCCUGUAAUUUCACUAAGUCAGUAUUUCUGUUAAUAAGACCAAAUUAAAAAGGCUAGUGGCUGUGUAGCAUCCUCAGUGCAAAACCCAGCUCCAGAAUUUUCACCUGGUAACGAAUUUCAACUGACAGUGAAAUGAAUAGGCCUUUAAACUUUAUAACAUUGCAAUUGUGAUGUUAUCUCUAGGUUUUUGUGUGAAGUCAUUCAAAAACUAUUUCAUUGUAAAUUAAUAAAAACAAUCCAUUUAACUUGUGAAGCUGAUUUGAUUGAAGAGGAAUCCAAAGCCCAUAACUAACAUCAAAAAUCAAACUGCAAUUAUGAAUUGAGAAAUAUGAAUAGCAUUUGUUUCACAUUGCUAGCACACAUGUGACACACCCACUUGUCUUUCAUUAUUGGAAAUCUAAAUCAAGUUUAAAAUGAGAACAGGAAGGACAUGUUUACUUCCUUUUUUGAGACGGUGCGAUCUCGGCUCACUGCAUCCUCAGCUUCCCAGGUUCAAGCGAUUCUCCUGCCUCAGCCUCCCAAGUAGCUGGGACUACAGGCGUGCGCCACCACGCCCAGCUAAUUGUUAUAUUUUUAGUAGAGACAGGGUUUCAUCAUGUUGGCUAGGAUGGUCUCAAUCUCUUAACCUCGUGAUCUGCCUGCCUCGGCCUUCCAAAGUGCUGGGAUUACAGGUGUGAGCCACCGCGCCCAGCCCGUUUACUUCAUUUCUUACUUUAAACUCCUAUUUCGAGUGUUUUAGUAAAACUAGAUCCUAAUAGCAGUGGCAAAGGACUCAUAGACAUGAAGUCCCACGAGUUAAAAGAUGACACACAAUGCUAUGUGUUCUGGCUGUUUAUAUCAGUUCAUGAUACUAGCAAUCCUGAUACCAGUAUUAGUUUAAUUCUUAUCCAGAAAAGAUAAACACAUGGUUCCUUGUCUACAAAGUAUUCGCCUGUUUCAAUCCAACCUUUGCCUGUGUGCCAGUAUGCAUUACUAUAAAGGGCAAGAGACUGUUGAGGGGACCAGUGUGGAUAUCUGCAUCAUUACCUUAUUGGGAAAAAAAAAAUCUAAUUCUACAGUCCGAUGAUGUUACUGCCAUCUCCUCUGAAAAUUCCAAGCUCCACAGGCUUCACCAGGCUUUUCAAAAUGAGAGUUUAUUUUAAUGAUUAAAAACCGCUAUUUAAGUAGCUCUUGCCAAGCCUUUUCAUUACCAGGUCUCCAUCCCUCCCCAAGUAUUUCUGCGAGUCUCAUGUGCUAAGAGAUGUCUUGAGCAGCCUCUGCAGCUUUCCGUGUUUCUGUGGUCAGCUACUGCUGCCCUUUCCCGGGAGGCAUUCCAUUCUCCUACUGGGUCCUCUCAAGAUGCCAAAGCUUGGUGCUGGGAUUUAGGAACACAUCCUGUUAGAUGUCAGACAGUGCUGCUUGUGCUGGGGAGCCUACAGAACUUCUGAUGAAACUACCAUCUGGUUUUACCCUCUGUGCCGUGGAUGCAGACGUGUCCUUGGGCUACAGAGAGGACAUGAUGGAGCAGGAGGCCCUAUCCCAAGGAGGUGUUAGAACUGGGUCCACUUUGUACUGCCUCUUUCUUCUUAGGUCACAAUGAGUGUCCUCUCAGGGCACAACUCAGAUCUUCAACCCAUGGCUCGCUGUAGGCCUGCCCCGCCAGGUCCUCCAGCUUGCCAUUCAUGUUUCCAUCCUAGCCUUGGUUGUGCUGGAACUCAGGCUGGAGCCUGACACUUUGCCUAUAUGCAAAGGGAAGAAAUAGGACUUACAUUGCCAAGGAAUCACUUCUUAAUGUUUGCCAGCACUAAAAACAACAAAGUAUAGGAAUCUUUUUCCCCCACAGUCUCCACAAAGCUAUCAAUAAGUAUAAUUCGCAUUUACAAGUUUUAGGCCUUCAACAGAUGUAACUCCAUCCAAAUGAAUCAAUAUGUGCCAUCAACCUACCUUAUAGAGGUGUUUUUCCUGAUUACAUGAGCAAAAGUAGCUACAGAAAGAUGGGUGUAAAGAAAAGGCAAUAAAUUCUAGGUUAUGAACUCUACUGCUUCUGGAGCUAUUUCUGAGAUUUUUCAGAACCUACUUUUUUAUAAAUAAGUCUAAUUUGAGCAUUCUGCAAUACUUUUUUUCCUAUCAGGAAAACUAAUGCAGAUAGUAUUAUGGGGACGUGUAGGUUUUAUAGAAAAAAAAAGUACAUGUAUAAUUCAAAACUCAACUUUGUAUGUAUAGGAGUCUGCUGGUUGUUUGCACAGCCUGAUAUGAGCACAUAAUAAAAGUCCGUCAUUCCCCAACCCCCUCCCCCUACACACACAGCUUAUUUUGGGAAACUGCCCCUUCCCUGUGUGAUUUGGGAAGAGAAAGUGAUAGGAAUCAAGUUGUCCUCUGGCAGCCUCCUGGAGAGAUGGCUGUGAGCUCUUGCUGCUUAAACCUCUAGUGCCACCCUCAUUUCUGACCUACUGAAUGCUCAGCUGUUUGGCAUUUCCUUUGAAUGACCCAGCAUCUUCCCUUUUGUUGUCGGAAAUCAGAAUCAGUCUCUAUUGCUUGUAACUUAAGAAUCUGGAUAUUCUGUUUAUUAUAUUCUUAAAUGGUUAUUUGGAAAAUGUGCUCAUUUAUAAAAGUUACAGUGUCUUUUUAAAGUUUGCUGAAGUAAAUGAAGCAUAUCGUCAAGUA